AGCCGCUUCCCGCCCCCGAGCAGGAGCCGGUGCGAGCGGAGCAGAGCCGAGGUCGGGCCGCGAGCGGAGCCGGCUGAGCGGGCGCCGAGCUCCCGCCAUGGCCCGGAACACGCUGUCCUCGCGCUUCCGCCGGGUGGACAUCGACGAAUUUGACGAGAACAAAUUUGUGGACGAGCAGGAGGAGGCGGCGGCGGCGGCGGCGGAGCCAGGCCCGGACCCGAGCGAGGUGGACGGGCUCCUGCGGCAAUAUCCUUCCCUGACGCGGCGUCCGGGCCUGCGCGCGGCCUUCUCACCUUCCCACCUUCCCACCUUCUCGGGCCCUUUCGGGCGGGCCUCCCCUGUCUCCGACCCUUGGCCCCCUCAGGAAAUCGGGCCUAUGGCGGGGCUGGGUCGGCGGCAGGGCGGAGGUGAGCCGCAUCUGAGUAACCGAGUGAUCGGGGAGGCUGGGGCGCGGUCCUCCGGGGCCCGAUUGCUGCAUGGCGUGAAGAUAGGUGGGUGGACGGCUGUGGGGAAGACAGAACCCAGGAGGGAGUGGAGGCGGCCGCCGUAUUUCAGCCCUGGGGUCUGAGAUUGUGUCUCUCUUCCCCCAGUCAGUCUAACCCUCCCGCUUAAUGCUGAGAAAGGGGGACCCUGUGGUUCCCCUGGACACCUUGGUGGUCUCAGCCACGCUCAACAAGUGAGUCUUGGCUCCCCCCAGUACCCUUCUGGUGCAGGAAGCAGCGGAGAAAACUAGUAGUUCAGAGCUAAGAAAAACCAGACACCUUGAAGCGAAGUGUGAAAGUGGAGCCCCACGCCUGGAAAUGACUGUUCUUGUGGCCACAGAAAACAGCAUUUAGAAAAGAUUAAAAAUAGAGGUGAUUGUCACAGCCUUGCUUGGUCCUUUAGCAGUAUGAGCGCAGGAAACUGACUUAUUCUCACCGGAAGGAUUUUUCUUUAUUCAAAUGGUGUUCCAGGAAGCCUGUCCCCUCCCCCCGCACGGGUGGGGGCAGGGUUGGAGGCCCAUGCUGUACAUAAAUCAGGUUCUCGGUGUUGAACCAGUUGACUCAGCUUGGAAAGUGGGGCCUGCUGCUUUAGGGGGAGCCCGGCAGUGCUCCUGAGUGUGCCUUUAAACCGAAAACCUUCAGACUUGAUUUGAACAGGAAUGUGUUUUCCGAAGUGGAGAUUCAAGCUUGUAAUUCCUGCCCCAUCAGGAUCUCCCAAUCCACCCUCCUUAUGAAAUGGGGUCAAGGGAAGGGUCCCCAGGAGGGAAGGUUGGUUGUAGUCUGGUGUAGGGCCUAGUUCAUGGACAGUCAGUGCUGAAAGGGGCUCCAGGGUCAGGCCUUUGGCCCAGGACUCUCAUUGAACAGAUGAGAUCAAGCCUGUCAGCUGCUGCCUUGGUCUGGGUGCAGAACCUUGUUGAAGGUCAUGUCUUGGGACUCCCCUGCCUGGUGACAGGUUCCUUGAGGCUGCUUAGAGGCCUGGGCUUAGCACAUCCAGGGGAUGGUCGUUUCUCCAUUCAUGGCAGCGUCAGAAGCGUCAGAAACCUUGUUACCAUGGAGAGUGCUCCACUUGGGGUUGGGGAAAGGGAGGUUAACGGAUAAAGGUAACUGAAACCCUGGCAAAUACGGGGCCCAGGUGGAGGAGAAUGGAACUGAUAUUUAUUGAGUCUCUAUCAUGUACCAAGAAUCGGACUUAUAUUAGACCAUUGAGGACAGGGGAGCAGGGAGAGGGAUAGAUGGAUUGGGGUUGGGGAGGGCAGAGAGGGGCCCUGUCCUGGGGCUGUAUAGGGAAGUGUGUGUGGCAGGAGAUGACACAGAUGGAGUAGAAGGAACCCGGCUGUGCAUCUGCGCACACCCUGCACUACCAUGCUCUGGCUCUGUGACCUCGGAUAGGUCGCAUACCCUUUCACAACUCAGCAUCUUCUGUUACGUGGCGGACAGCCAUGCUGGCUUCCUAGAUUCCGUGGGAGCCUCAUGGGCUAACAUCAGCAUCACUGGGCACACAGCAAGUGUCCUGGACAUGCAGCUCGGGUCUGCAGAUAGAGCGGCAGCAUGGGAUUGUGGGAGGAGCUUGGGUGUGAGGGCCGUGUAGACAGCUUAGUUUUGUGACCUUGCGCAGGUAAUUUCUGUUCUCUGAGCCUCAAUUCCAUUGCCUUUAAAAUGAGAUAAUGAUUAUUGUCACAAGGAUUUUUGGAAUGAGAUGGCGUGUGAAAGCACCUGGCACAGGAUCCGAGACCUUGUGGCGAUUUAAAAGUAUGAGUUCCUUUCCCCUUCAGUGAAGCAGCUUCUAUACUUCUGGAUCAGGGCUCUGUCCAGAGCAGUGGUUGUGAGCGAUUUUGCACCCUUCCCCUCCACCCCCAGGAAACUGGAGACAUUUUGAUGGUUACAGCUUGGGGAUGCCACUGGAAUCCAGUGGGCAGAGGCCUAUGACACACAGCUAAGAUCCCACGUCAGAGAAUCCUGGGUCCACAGUGUCAGUUGUGCCGUGAUUGAGGAAGAUCUAGAGGAGAUCAAGGGCUGGGCAGGAUUCCCUCAGCACCACAGCCUGUUCUCUGAAAAGGCCUAAAGCCAGCCAAGUAUGACAGCCGGCUUCACAAAUGAUAGGUGACUUCAGGGAGGUCCUCCCUGCGCCCCACAUCUCCCAACUGCUGAAGGCCCUCACCCAUCAAUGGGCCGAGUGAUUGCUGGACGCGUGGUGCUGAGUUAACGCCACAGCAGUAGCUUUUUGCCCCCGUGGACUAGUUUUAUACCUGCCCUUCCCCAUCCAUCAUUUGAAUGAUGUCAUUUGUUAGUUGUGCCAGGUUUACAUGAAGAGCAAGUGAGCCUAUGUUUUCUGUUCAGCCUAUGGGAUCCUGCUUAUUGCUUUGGGGACACCACAUUAGAAAAGAGUUACAAGGGCUGGGCGCGGUGGCUCACACCUGUAAUCCCAGCACUUUGGGGAGGCCGAGGCGGACAGAUCACGAGGUCAGGAGAUCGAGACCAUCCUGGCUAACACAGUGAAACCCCGCCUCUACUAAAAAUACAAAAAAAAUUAGCUGGGCGUGCUGGCGGGCGCCUGUCGUCCCAGCUACUCAGGAGGCUGAGGCAGGAGAAUGGCAUGAACCUGGGAGGCGGAGCUUGCAGUGAGGCAAUAUUGCGCCACUGCACUCCAGCCUGGGCGACAGAGCGAGACUCCGUCUCAAAAAAAAAAAGGAGUUACAAAGUAGAGGUUAUCAGUGGCUGAUAUCAGGCUGGCCUUGUUUGGAUGGGGAAAAGGAACUCCAGAACUGAAAGACAGAGGGACUGGACUGCCUCUUGAGUGUGGAAGGUGGAUCAGAGCCAAGCAGGGAGCUGGGGAACCAGCGCUGGGAGUGGCUUGCCUGGUGGCGCAGACCCAGCUCACUCAAGAUGGAUCUCAUACUGGGGAAGCCAGGAGAUUCAGCUCUGCUCCGAAGGCCCUUCCUGUCUGCACGUGGGUAUCACUGCAUGAAGAGGAGUAGAGACCCGAUUGGGCAGAAGCCAUUCCUUGUUCUAUUUUUGAAGCUUUUUGGCUGAAGCCAGUGUUUCAUACGAGGAAAUGAAAGUUGGCUGAUGUAAUUCAGUUUAAAAUAGGUGUCACCUUUGGGGACCUAACCCAGAUUGUAAUUUUCUUUUGCAUGCUGGGUAUUCAGAACUCAGCAAAGAAUGUGUUGUCAGGAUUGCAACUGAGGUUGGGGGGUAAGGGUGGAGACUGGCUCAUUGUUGGCAAAAGCUUCUGUUAGAUUGAUAAACUCUUUCCAGGUAACAGUUGGGACCUCAUUGAUCCCGAUAGAUCUUAGAAGUUCUAGCACAUCUUAAUUUCCUUAAUAGUUUAAUUGAUGAAGAGCAUUGAUGAAGAGUUAGGAGGUCUCCCUUUGUACCUACAUUUUCCGCUUUUUUAGAAUGAGAAGAUGAGAACGACCUCCAGUUCACAUGUACGGGUGCUGUGAGGAUCCAGUAGGGGAGAUACAGUGCUCAGCACCAAGCAGGUGCAAGUGAGCACAAUCCAAUUUUACAUCAAGUUACCCCUCCAGGACAGUUGCUUUGACGUGGAAGGUAGAGAGGGAGUUGAAAGGAGGGUUUGCAUGGUUGGCAGAGGUGCCCUGCAGCCUCCCUGUGCAGGCUGUAAACCGUCUCUGCCCCCCUGGAAGCCGUGGAAGGUGGGUGGUAUGGAUGAGAUCCCAUCUGACUCUGUUCCUGAGCUGUUUCUGAAGUGAGCUUGUUCAUGACGGCAUGGAUGUGCUUGAGCCUAGCUAUCCUUAACUGGUGGU